ACUCGCUGAGGCCCCGACGCAGGGCCGGGCCGGGCCCAGGGCCGAGGAGCGCGGCGGCCAGAGCGGGGCCGCGGAGGCGACGCCGGGGACGCCCGCGCGACGAGCAGGUGGCGGCGGCUGCAGGUGAGCACCGAGGCCCCCACCCGAGGUCGGGCCGCCCCCCUCUUCCCCCACGCCCCGCCGCCGCCCGAGGUCGCCCUCCCGCCGCCGGAGGUCGCCCCUGCCCCAGCCGUCCGACCUCGGGCCGCCCGGGGCCCCGCGCCGCAAUGGGCCGGCCGCGCUCCGCGGGGCGCGGGGCCUGGGAAGGCGCGGGGCCGGGAGGAGGUCUGGGCCCGGGUCCUGUGCGCCCCCCGCAACCCCGGCCUCCCCGGCGGCCUGGUCCAGCGCGAGGCCCCGGCCGCUUCCCGCAGCAGCCUCGGUGGCGCUGGGCCCAGCGGGGAGGCCCGGGGGUUCGGGGCGCCCGGGAGGGGCCCGGGCCGGGCCGAGGGAGGGCGAGUGGGUUCCCGCGGGGACGUCCCAUCCCUCCGUCCUGGACUCUGCUCCGGGCCCCGCUCGGCUCCCCCGUGGACAGGACGCGCCCGCCGCCUGGUUUCGGGGCGCGGCGGACCCGGGACCCCCCCCAGGGGCCUCCUCCUCGCGCGCCCAGGCCAAGGGAGCAGUUUCACUUUUGCCGCUCCGCGCGGGGAGGGCUGCGGGGCCCGGGGUUGGCUGUGGGUUCGGCCCGGAGACCGGCGGCGCGUUUGCACCGGGCGGGUCAGGGGAUGGGGUCAGUCCGGGGGCAAGAGCCGUGGGGGCGAAAACCCACUCCUGGCCACCCCAGGACCCUUGGAACAUUGGUCCCAAGUACUUAGGAAAGGAGGGUUAUUAGUAUUUGAAGGCAGUUAAAAAUGGUGCAGUGUUUUUUUUUUUUUUUUUAACUUUGAGAGAAGUUUAGUGACAUGGGGAAAAUGCUUUUAUAAAUGGCUUCCCAGACCUUUAAAAAAAAAAAAGCACAAUUUUAAAAGCUUUGUCUAGGAGAAUACUUGAGCAGUUGGGUUCUUUUUCCUGGGAAACAUGAUCUUAGUAGAAGAAAGAUGUGGGCUGUUGGCCUCCAGACAGAGGGUGAUGAGCAUGCGGCUCUUAUUAAAAAUGAAAGCCAACGCCGAGAGCCUGCUGGGGGCUGGGAGGUGGGGCGGGCGGCGGGCCCAGGCUGCUAGAGGGACCCAGGAUCCUGCAGCUUUUAAAUUGCAGGCGCGGCUGCUCCGACUCGACUCGCUUAGGAAUUGCUGAACUUCGUCUUCUCAGUUUGAAAGCUUCAGAGGGGUCUCCCGAGGAUGCUGAGCACUCUCUUGAUUUGGCCACUUCUUUGCCGCCCCCCCUCCCUCUUUCCAACCAAUCCUCCUCCCCCACAGAGUUCGGCGUUAGCCUGUGCCUGUUACAACUCGCUUCUUGUAUCCAUUUCUGACACGUGACUGAUACACCUGCCUCCCAUCCCCUCCGCACUUUGACCUCGUAAACAAGUGAUCUGACACAACAGGGCUUGAGUUACUUGCCCGAGGUUGUGUCACGGAACGGCAGGGCCGCCUUUAGGCUUACAUCCCUGGAACUCCCACCUCCACAGACCCGUCCGGGUGCUGAAAGUCCACGGAUGCUAUCCCUGGUCAAAUCAGAGGACGGCUGUCCUCAGCGAGGGGCCGUGCACCCGCUCCUGAGCAGCGCCAUGGGCCUGCUGGCCUUCCUGAAGACCCAGUUCGUGCUGCACCUGCUGGUCGGCUUUGUCUUCGUGGUGAGUGGUCUGGUCAUCAACUUCGUCCAGCUGUGCACGCUGGCGCUCUGGCCGGUCAGCAAGCAGCUCUACCGCCGCCUCAACUGCCGCCUCGCCUACUCACUCUGGAGCCAACUGGUCAUGCUGCUGGAGUGGUGGUCCUGCACGGAGUGUACACUGUUCACGGACCAGGCCACGGUAGAGCGCUUUGGGAAGGAGCACGCAGUCAUCAUCCUCAACCACAACUUCGAGAUCGACUUCCUCUGUGGGUGGACCAUGUGUGAGCGCUUCGGAGUGCUGGGGAGCUCCAAGGUCCUCGCUAAGAAGGAGCUGCUCUACGUGCCCCUCAUCGGCUGGACGUGGUACUUUCUGGAGAUUGUGUUCUGCAAGCGGAAGUGGGAGGAGGACCGGGACACCGUGGUCGAAGGGCUGAGGCGCCUGUCGGACUACCCCGAGUACAUGUGGUUUCUCCUGUACUGCGAGGGGACGCGCUUCACGGAGACCAAGCACCGCGUUAGCAUGGAGGUGGCGGCUGCUAAGGGGCUUCCUGUCCUCAAGUACCACCUGCUGCCGCGGACCAAGGGCUUCACCACCGCAGUCAAGUGCCUCCGGGGGACAGUCGCAGCUGUCUAUGAUGUAACCCUGAACUUCAGAGGAAACAAGAACCCGUCCCUGCUGGGGAUCCUCUACGGGAAGAAGUACGAGGCGGACAUGUGCGUGAGGAGAUUUCCUCUGGAAGACAUCCCGCUGGAUGAAAAGGAAGCAGCUCAGUGGCUUCAUAAACUGUACCAGGAGAAGGACGCGCUCCAGGAGAUAUAUAAUCAGAAGGGCAUGUUUCCAGGGGAGCAGUUUAAGCCUGCCCGGAGGCCGUGGACCCUCCUGAACUUCCUGUCCUGGGCCACCAUUCUCCUGUCUCCCCUCUUCAGUUUUGUCUUGGGCGUCUUUGCCAGCGGAUCACCUCUCCUGAUCCUGACUUUCUUGGGGUUUGUGGGAGCAGCUUCCUUUGGAGUUCGCAGACUGAUAGGAGUAACUGAGAUAGAAAAAGGCUCCAGCUACGGAAACCAAGAGUUUAAGAAAAAGGAAUAAUUAAUGGCUGUGACUGAACACACGCGGCCCUGACGGUGGUAUCCAGUUAACUCAAAACCAACACACAGAGUGCAGGAAAAGACAAUUAGAAACUAUUUUUCUUAUUAACUGGUGACUAAUAUUAACAAAACUUGAGCCAAGAGUAAAGAAUUCAGAAGGCCUGUCAGGUGAAGUCUUCAGCCUCCCACAGCGCAGGGUCCCAGCAUCUCCACGCGCGCCCGUGGGAGGUGGGUCCGGCCGGAGAGGCCUCCCGCGGACGCCGUCUCUCCAGAACUCCGCUUCCAAGAGGGAGCCUUUGGCUGCUUUCUCUCCUUAAACUUAGAUCAAAUUUUUUGGUUUUUAAUCAGUUAUCUUGGGAACUUAACCUGGCCCCUCACCUCUUCUGCACCCCCCGCCCCCGAAACUGUCUCGUAAUGAAUUUCUGCUGUCCUCCUGGGAGUGGACGGCCGGGUCCCGUCCCCCGGGAGCAUCGCUCGGCUCAGCACCUUGGCUCCCAGUGGGGGCCCCGUGGAGGGCGCCCGUAGUGAUAAGCACACCGGCACGAACGUCAGGUCCAUUCCUCGAAGUCGGAGCCCUCACUCUGCCCUGUCCUGGGGCUGGCUGAGGGCGAACGCCCCACCUCACUUUCUAGAGCCCUGUCUGUCCUAGCUCCUAUCUGACCUUGUGUGUAAAUACGUACAUCUGUUUUUAAAGUGGAUGGGCCCCUGAGAACUCAGUGAAAUGCAGAGUUCUCCAUGCACCUAAAGCUCCUUUGUCGCUCUCAUGGCUGUCAGAUCCUGGUCCCUCCACACUGGGUGCUGGGGAGGGAGGACCCUCGGGGCUACCGCGCGCCCCCCCAUCCCACAGAUCAGGAGCCAAGGAGGGAGAACAGGGCAGCCUGUGGGACUCUAGGAUGCUUCAGAAGAAGCGACGGCACCGUCAACCCUCUGUUUUUUAAAGGUGGUUGGAGACUGUUAACACUGAGCUCAUUGACUUCUAGAGAUUUUAUUUUUACUGGUUGAUCUCUUGGUGGUUUUCAACUUCCUGCUGGAAACUAGAGGUGGGGCACCCCCCACCCCCCAGCCUCGCACUGUGUCCUUGGGGAAGGCCCGCCCCCAUCCUGGCCGGUGUCACUGUGGCCCGGCCACCCCUGAGCGCCCAGCUCCCUACCUCCUGGACGUCUCUGAGAGUCCAGGCAGAGCAGAGGGCAGCGCUCGGCCGGUCAUGCUGGCUCCCUUGGCCUUGCAGCGAGCCCCUGGCCCACGCCGAGCGAGGGAUGCUUCUCCCUACAGCAUGUCCACUCCCCCGGCAUGGCCAGGUGGGGCCCCUGGGGCAAUGGCAGUGGUAGAACGCUCAACUUGGUUGCGGUACCAUCAGCCCACCUGCAUUUGGCUUUCGACUUGCUUGUUCUAAGUCACAGCGCCCUCAUCUUUUUAGCAAGGUAAAAAAACCAAAAUGGGUGUUAUCUCUGAUAUCUUGAAACCAGCGUUCUGAAUAGAGGUAGGUUGAGUUUUCUAGGGGAAAACAAAUGGAGAAAAGAGGCAUGAAGAAAAGUAAACCGAGAACAUAAUUAGGCAUCGGGCCUAAGUGUCCUGGGGAGAUUGGAGGGGACGGCAGCGUUCUGCAUGAUGGAGGCGCUGCCGGGCCCCGGGUCUGUGGGGGCCGUGCUCUCAGGGCGUGUGCGGGACGCCACCUGUGCACACCUGCUCAGAGCACGGCUCCUCGCAGGGGUGAAGGGGCAGACCAACGAAACCAGAUGAGACCAACGACACCAUGCGAGACACGCUUGCAGACACUGUUGUUUUGGAAAUGUGCUUCCCUCCAUCUGAAAUCUCAUCCCUCCACCCGCCCACUCGGGCAGCUGUGCCGUGGGCAGGGCAUGCGCUCCCCUGGCUGAGCACCCCAGAGAUUCUCCUGCACCUUCCUCAUGCCGCACGCUGCUCAUCCGUCUCCAUGUGUGUUUAGAUCCAUGCCAUUCACUGACUCACUAACACCUGCAAAAUCUUUAAGGAAAAAAGCUGAAGGGUACGACCAUGCACAUAUGUGACCUGGAAAAUGCAAAUUUAGAUCUUUUAUGAUUUAAUUAUUAUUGUUUCCCAUAGAAGUUCCCUCCCUUUGAAAUUAAUAUAUAAUGUAUAAAUUCUGCACUGAGCCAUGGCGGAGCUGGGCAGCCCCUAGGUUAGAGUGGAGACGGAGGCCCAGGCGCAGGGGUCACACCUCAUCUGGUUUCCUUCCCAUCUCACAGCUUAGCUUGUGCUUCUCAACACCAAGUCUUUAAGAGCAAUAAAAACUACACCAUGAAUGUUUGAAUUUUUUUUUUUUGGGGGGGGGAGGGUGGAUUUUGCUUUUCAUCCAGAAGGAAAAGGGGAGGAGAGCUCCUUUACAUUUUUUAAAUUAAAUUCAUAAAUCCCAGAACAGUCUUUUUUUUUUCUUUUUCCUUUACACCCUACUUCUGAGCUUAAUUCAGUUGAUGUUAUGUCCAAAUUCAGGCUGAGUGCUCAGGCUGAAGCAACUCUGUAGCCCACAGUCCGUGCUGGCCACUGUCGGGGUGAGGCACAUUCUAGGCCUGGCAUCGCUGAUGCCCUCUGCACCCAGUCCUUGAGCCAGGCCGAGGACAGGAAGGGCAUUGCUGGCCUGUAGCUCCUGUUACCCACCCAGAGCCAGGCGCCACACUGGAGGCUCCCAGGCGGGAGGGCCCAGGCCCACCCACGGGCGUCUGGCCGGUCAAGCUCCCAGCCUGGGCCGUGGUCUCCUGGGGACGCCGCUGGCCUCCCAGCUUAGGCCCAGGUGCCAGGUGUCAUGGGGUCUCCUGCCCAUCUUCCCAAGGAUGCCAUUGCUGUCUUCAUCGUCUUCCCCCGUGUGAGACACUGGUUGUCUGGUACUCGGCGACAGUGUACCAGACGCGCACCCUAUGUGAGGUGCUUUAAGGUCCCUGUCCUCAGGAAGCGCAGUCUGGUGGAAGAGAUGAGCGCUGAACAAAUCACUAAAUAACACAAAACAACAAUGUAAGCAGCACUUUCUUGUGUAAAAAAAAAAAAAAAGCACGUCCUGUCGAUGAAUUUUGAGUCUCUCUGCCUUGCCUGUCCCGACUCCCUUUCGCGCACCGUGGCAUGAGAAUCUUUCCUCACGCUGUUCGUUGCGGUAUUGCUGAGCAUUGAUGUUGAUUUGAAGGAAAAGCCGUGGUUGGACCCAGCUGUGUGUUUCACUCACGUGCAAUUGAGUAGCUGUUGCCAGGCUGUCCAUGCCUGUUGUGACUACCGGUUGGGGUCAGAUUUGGGGUGAAGAAUGAGUAAGUUUCUGCAUGCUUUGUCUCUACCUGAGACACUUCUACAACAAGCCAAGUAUAAUCUCUCCAGCCCUGCAGAUUUUCACCUGACUUGUUCAGCCCCAUGCGUAGACUCCCGCUGCAGGCCUCUGGCCUGUGGCUCACUGCAUGCAGCCCCUGGCGUGCAAUACUAGUGCUCCACGGCGCGAUGUGCUUCUAGCCCUUGCACUGCACCUAGGCUCAGGGUUCAAACGGCCAGCCCGAAAAGCCUGCCUGCCUUCUUUCUGGAAACAGCACGUCCCCGGCCGUGUGCCUGCCCCUUUCUCUACUGAGCUAGUCCCCAAACCAAAGGCAAGCCCCCUCGGGCCUCGGGGGAUGGGGCCGGCCACACCCCUGACUCCGCCCUGGCUCUGCCCCAUACCCCUGCCGUGGGGCCGACCUGGGGGAUGCAGACAUCCGGCUCCGUAUUCCUGCCUAUCGGGGCCAGGAUGCAAAAACAAUUUUUGCGUAAAAGAUGUCACACUGAUCUGCUGGAGUGGGGUGGACACAUGAAUUCAGUUUUAUCAUGAACACUCGCCACUGGCUGCUUGUUAAUUCAGGGAUAAUGGUGGCAUUCUUACAAACUGCUCGGGAAAUAGAAUGACGGGAACACUUUUAGGGAGCCCAGGAAGUUACCAGGGACAUUGGUGUCGCCGGCCCAGGCAACAGCAGCGUACGCUUUUCAAAGAUCAUUGAGUUGUCUUAGAAUUUGAAGCUGUGUAAUGACAAUGUCACCUGGAGUUCGUCUCCAUUUCUUAACUUUUUGUUGCACAAGUAUUUGGACAGAAGUCGAACUGUGAAUGAGAUACUGAAAUGCACUAAAUUGUAUUACAUUAAACUGGAGUUACUUGAUACAAUGAAGAAAUGCAUCUGAUCUACUUGUAUUUAUUGUCUCAGAAUUGUACGUUGUGACAAUCAAAUGUUACUUGCCUAAAUGCCAGGAAAUUCAACUGGCCUUUUAAUCAGCAAGAUCGCCAGCAAGUACUGUAACUGUAAAGGAAAAUCUCUCUCUCUGGAGAACCCACACAAACCAUUGACCUGAGUGCGCAUGACAGCCACUGGCUUCUUUUUCUAUGAUUGAAAAUCUGCCAUCGCUGACUGUUGGCCAGUUUCAAAGGGACCCAUUGUAUACAGGGUGCAAAUGUAUUAUACGGAUGUUUCCUUUUGUACACUUCAUUUUUACAAGUUUUGCUACUCACAAGCUUUAUGUAGUGGAGGAUAGAGGUAUUUUUGGUCUUUAGAAGCUUGUCGGGGUGAGGGCUGCUAACUUACACUUCAGAGGCCUGUGUCCCAAAGGCCUGGCUGCGUUUGCCGUGCUGUGCGAGGACCUGUGUACACAGGCAGGUGUGCGCCUGCCCGAGCGCGAGUAGCUCUUGUGUAGUGGUGAAAUGCUGCAGGCAUCUGUUUAUUAAAAUUGCUGCUGUGAAAGACAGGGAUAAAAUAUCCACAAUAUAAGAGAAAGCGACUCCGUGCCUCCUUCUGUUUCUUCGUUUCCAGUCUGCAUAGAUGUCUCCAAGGGGAAACCAGGGCCACCAGGCACUCCUGUCCCAUGGGGCCACCCACCUUCAGAGCCCACUCCCACGGGCUCUGUUUCCUUGGAGGCCAUCCUGCCGAUGGCACUUUUCAAGGCCCUCCCUUCCCUACGAGUUGCUUUCUGGGAGGGGAAAUUGAAAAGGAGAGCGGUCACCUGGCAAAAACACAGGGGAAAUCAGCCAGUCCACAAAAAUACGCAAAAUGACCUGAUGAUGUCCAAAAAAGGGUUUUAAAAGCGAUCAAGGACAAAAGGUUUUCCUAAGUGGCAUGUAUACAUCCAAAACUACUCUUUUUUUGUAAAAACAUUCAUCUGUGGAGAAAACCAAGGAACCCCUUUCUCUUCUUUAUUAAAAAGCAAAACAAAAACUCUUGUUAGAACCAAAA